CUUCUUAAGCAGCCUGUGGCCGGGCACAGUAGCUCACACCUGUAAUCCCAGCACUUUGGAAGGCCGAGGUGGGCGGAUCACCUGAGCUCAGGAGUUUGAGACCAGCCUGUCUCUACUAACAAUAUAAAAAUUAGCUGGGAGUCACGGUGGGCGCCUGUAAUCCCAGCUACUCGGGAGGCUGAGGCAGGAGAAUUGCUUGAACCCAGGAGACAGAGGUUGUAGUGAGCUGAGAUCGCACCACUGCACUCUAGCCUUGGCAACAGUGCAAGACUGUCUCAAAAACAGCAACAGAGAGCAGGACGUGAGACUUCUACCUGCUCACUCAGAAUCAUUUCUGCACCAACCAUGGCCACGUUUGUGGAGCUCAGUACCAAAGCCAAGAUGCCCAUUGUGGGCCUGGGCACUUGGAAGUCUCCUCUUGGCAAAGUGAAAGAAGCAGUGAAGGUGGCCAUUGAUGCAGGAUAUCGGCACAUUGACUGUGCCUAUGUCUAUCAGAAUGAACAUGAAGUGGGGGAAGCCAUCCAAGAGAAGAUCCAAGAGAAGGCUGUGAAGCGGGAGGACCUGUUCAUCGUCAGCAAGUUGUGGCCCACUUUCUUUGAGAGACCCCUUGUGAGGAAAGCCUUUGAGAAGACCCUCAAGGACCUGAAGCUGAGCUAUCUGGACGUCUAUCUUAUUCACUGGCCACAGGGAUUCAAGUCUGGGGAUGACCUUUUCCCCAAAGAUGAUAAAGGUAAUGCCAUCGGUGGAAAAGCAACGUUCUUGGAUGCCUGGGAGGCCCAGCUUAUACUCUACCUGAAGGACUCCCCUGACAACUGCGGGCUGUAUGUAUCUCUUCUUUCUCUGCCCUUUCUGACUCUGUCUAUGCCGCUGUGAUGUUAUCUGAGGCAGCCUCAGUGUCAUGAUUGAUGGCUCCAUAGAAGGGAACUCUAGCACUUUAAUUGGACUAUAAGAAUCCCAGAAAAAGGGAGCACAUUGUAUACAUUUACAUCCUGACAACUUCUGGGCAGGAUCUGGAACAUGUAAUAGAUGGCUACUAAAUACAUAUUGCACUGGAGGCUGCUGCUAACAUGUAUGGUAUCUUUGGGCAAGUUUGGAAAAUGCCCAAUAUAGGCUAAAAAUUAUACAAAGAUUCCCUUCCUUGCGUGUCCAUGCAGUUUCUGUACCAGGAAGCAUGGCUGGAUAUGCAAACAGUGGGUCAGGCUUCAGUCCCACACAACUCCAUGGCCGGGUGCCCCUAUCAGGGUGUAAUCUGAAUGCAUGACCUUCCUGCAAACCAAAGCAUGCUUAGUGUGGGAGAGAGGGACUCAGGACCCACAAGUGAGGCUUCUCCGUAUGCUGCAGCCUCUUCCUGACUAACACAGCUUGCCCAGGUUUGGGUGUGCAAUGCACACACACAACAGCAGCUCCCUGCUAUCAUUUGGAUUCAUUAAAAAUUAAAUCAUCUCAUAAGCUUACAAAUGUUGAUUUUUAUUUACUUUUUAUUUUUUUGCAUUACAAAACUUUCAUAUUUCCCCUGUGUACAGGAAGUUUAAUUUUUUAUGUGUUUCUUCACGUGUAAGGUGAGAGUGGCAAGAACAUAAAAUCUUUACCUGUUACUCCUAGUUUUUCUUGCGCUGGGGAGGGGCAGUAGGGCUGGAACCAGUCACUGAUGGGCACCCAGGCCCUGGACUAAAAUUUCCUGUGAAUGCUUCGGCUAACCCUGUUACGGUGGAUCCUUUAGCAAUUUCUGCCCCAGGGAGGACUAAGGCAAGCCAGGGUCCCUGUAGUCCCUCUAGAGCUGCCCAUAAGGUAUUCCUU